AGGAGGCUGGGUGAGGCGCUGAGACGGUUUGGCGGUGAGUCCUGGGCCAGGCGCAGCUGAAAGGCCCGCAACCCGGGAAACGUCAAAACAAACAGAAGGACUUGGGAUUCCGGAGCAGUCGCCCCUAUCGCUGCUCCUGCAGUUGCGGACGCCACCGACCCCGCCGCCGGAGGACUGGGCACUGAAAGGCCUCUAGGCCUAGGCGCGGCCCGCGGAGCCAGACGUGUUGCUGCCGUGAGUAAAACGAGCGCCCUCUCCGCACUCGUUUACAAAUUAAAAUGGAGGAAAUUUCGUUGGCCAACCUGGAUACUAACAAGCUAGAGGCCAUCGCUCAGGAGAUUUACGUAGACCUGAUAGAGGAUUCUUGUUUGGGAUUCUGCUUUGAGGUGCACCGGGCAGUCAAGUGUGGCUACUUCUACCUGGAGUUCGCAGAGACUGGUAGCGUGAAGGAUUUUGGCAUUCAGCCAGUGGAAGACAAAGGAGCGUGCCGCCUCCCGCUUUGCUCCCUUCCCGGAGAACCUGGGAAUGGGCCUGAUCAGCAGCUGCAGCGCUCACCUCCGGAAUUCCAGUAGCUGCAAAAUGAGAGUCUGAAAGUGGCCAGGACAAUAACAUAGACUGGUCCUGUGGCUUCGAGGAGUAAGCUAAGUAGAAAAAAGUAGAAAAAUCAGACAAAAGUUUUAAUUCCCCCUUGAAGAUCCUAGCAUUUAAAAACCCAAAGUGGAUAAUUUAGGAAUCCUUUUUUUAAAGUGUAUUACCUGGAGCAAGCUCUGAAGCCCUGGGCAGGAGGAGCUGCACAGCCUGCGGGCCAUGCAGUGCCUGUUGAUCUCUAAACACACCAGGAUGUGCGCAAGAUCCUGUAGUGCCCCCAGUGCACAGGUGAGCAGUUGUGUGCCCAGCAUAUAAAAUUUUUGGUUCCUCAGCCUUUCUGUCUGCCUGAUGUCAAGGGCUUCUUGGACAGUUUGGACGUUACAGUUCGUCAGGCCGUGAUCAGUGGCCUGCAGUGGGACUGCUCCUUUGAUAUCUGAACCUCUGUUAUGGGCUUCUCUGAGACAAGUAAAUGUCAGGUGCAAGAUCUGGAUACUAACAGUUUCAGUUUGGGAAAUCCAAGAAAAAGAAUUAUCAAGUUUGAUAGGGAAGCUCUGUAGCCUUGACUCCAGCAAGAAGAAAAGGUCAAAACCACGUGUUUCCCAAAAGUCCAGACUACAAUGAUUCAGCUGACUUGAGGACAAGGCCUAGCAUUUGGCUGAGCAGAGCCCUCUUCCUUGCCCUCCAACCUGGUGGCAUAGGCUUGGCAAAUGGACAACUUGGUUGUCCAGACAGGUUGAGGAUUCGGUUAUGAUCCCCUGGGGAGGUAGCAGGGACCUCUGCAACUAUGCAUGAUUUCUCAAACUUCAAGAUUCAUGUCUGGAUGUAUUAUGCUGUGGAUAUAAGUUUAGUAGGGCGGUCAUUUCCUACUCUGAGUUACUGGUUACCUAGCCAGUCCAUGGGUGUGACUUGGUCCUUAAGUCAGGUCACUAUCUGCCUCCCACCCUGGGGGCAGGACUGAAGUAUGGAAGAGCAUCAUGGCUGUGCAGGAGGCUGUGGUUUGAAAACUGAGCCCAGAGGGCACUUUCAGCUGCCCUCAAUAAUGUGAAUGGAUUAGUGCUAGGAGCCAAGGAGCAGGACUGGAUUAUCUCAUCUGACUGUGUGCAGAAUCCUGUUGAAUGUCCCUGUUUUCUUUGGUUGGGCAGUCAGAGCUCUGCUAUGGUGAACAUCCAGACUGUCACCACUUUCUGUCUGCCGCUCGAAAGGGAUAGUCCUUUCCACUCGGUCCCCUUUGGAUCUUCUUGACAACAGGAGCAGUCCUUUUAUUGUUAGAAGUCAGAGAAAGACCUCCAGAAUCUCCUGACUUUAGGGAAUGGUAUAGGGGAAGAUGGGAAGUAAGAGUCACAUAUCAAAACUACCCUCCACUUUAUUCCCUGAGCGAGGGUUUAUGAAGUAUAAAGGGGUGGGAGCCCCGAGGUGAGCGGGAACGGUGCUGCUUUAUUUGAAAUGUUUUCUUACCUCAUUCUGUGCCCCAGUAGGGGGUCCAGCCUCAUCUGUCUGGCUUGGCCCUGUGUUCCUCCUGUCCCCUGCUCCACUGCCUAUCUGGUGCCCCAGGUGCUGCUUGCCACUCCAGCUGUCACAUUGAACAGUUUCAAUUCAGCUCUUAAUGCUCCUGCUUCCGAAGCCUGCCCAAUUUCUUUUUUCUUGGCCUCUGUUUUUUUUUUUUCUUUCUUUUUCCCUUGUUUUUGUAGAAGACUCAGAGGAGAAUCUUUCUUAUGGCUCCCUCUGUUGAGAUUGGAAUUGGAAGAGAACUUAAUUUUUUGUAUUUAAAAUGCAGUGUCAUGCCUAUAAGCAUUUCUCCUAUAUAGGACUGCUUUGCUAGUGUGCCCUCUUGCUGUGUCUUACUUCAUAAGGAGUUGUAUCUUCCCACCUCCAUUUCAAUACUGCCGGUUAGGACCUAAGUAGAAGAGCAGUAAAGGCUGAUUGACACACAGGGGGAUGGAGUUGGUCCUUGUCCAUUCUCUCACCCUUGCUGUGCAUGUAUCAAUCCUUAUCCCAGAAGGUACUAUUUAGACUGUAUAGACUGAUUUAGAUUACAUACUUUAGAGGAUUAAGGAAACCAUAGAGUUUGGGCCUUGGAACUGUUACUGCCUUGUCCUAGAGUUGUCCUGAUCAGGCUUGGGGCCUAGUUACAGAUUAGUCUUAAAGAAUUGCAUUAACUUAAAAAAAAUCAAACCUUGGCAAGAGCUAAAAUAAUUUGGAGAUAUCUUUGCCCUUGACUUGUAGACGACAUCUAAGAGGAUGAAGAAAGGAGAGUCUAAGUGAGACUCUGGCCUACUUCCUAACAAUGUCUUGGAAGUGGGAUGAUGGUAAAGGAGAAAGGCCACAGUCCAAUCCCUCUGCCUUCAGAUAGGGAACUCAAAUCCUGAAAUUACUGUUUUCUUUCUGGCCUUUUCUCCUGGUUAGAGGAGGAAGCGGAAAGUAGUUUUGAGUAGUAUUUUGUUCAUAUUACCCCCCUUUUGUUUUUUGUUUCUGGCCCCUCUACCAAUAGGGCAGUAGCCUCCUGCCCUGGAUGGGUAUAAGGUGGGCUUGGUCCAACAGGUGCCCAGAGGGUACAUACUCCUUUCUGGGGAGAGAAUGCUCCCUACCAUAUAGUUGACAGUGGUUAGGAACUCUCCCUUUCCCUACCUACCUUCCUUUUAAUAGCAGAAUUCCUAUUUUUCCCUUGAUUAUGUGUAUUGAUCACCCUGCAAUCCUAUUAUGUAUCUGAGUGUGUGUGUGUGUGUAUGUGUGUGUUAUGGGGGAAGGGGGGGGUUCUUUAAAAUUUCUGUGGUUUGUGGCUUUUUCUUCCAUACAUUAGUUCCCACCAUCGCAUGCCCAGGGACCACUGCCUGGCAUUAUCGCAUGCUGGGAUCAUCGGGGGAGGGUAGUGAAGCUCACCACUGUCCUUUGUUUUGGAGAUUUUUAUUUUUGCAUAAGUAGUCCAUCCUAUACAGAUAGCUGAUUAACUGUAUUCCCCUUUCCCCUAUGGCUGCUGGUGUAAAUAAACUGCAUCUCCCCAUUGGUAAACAGUAAUAAAAUUUUAAAAAAUGACUACUUGGUCCUUGGACUCUGUAUAUUCAUCUUUUAAAGCUGUAUGUUUUCAGGCAUUGACAUAAUGAGAUAAACGUUGAAAUGCUAUUGAACCUUAAUACUUCCUCCCUAACAGGAGUUUUAUCAGAACAGAGAAACUGUCCAACCUUGUUUCUCAAUUUGGCCUGCAAAUUUAACUGUCUGUAGCAUCCAGUGAAAGAGCCAAACCGUAUACAAUCAUCCCUUUUCCAUAUGAGGUAAGAAGGUGGUAAGAUAAAUCCAGUCCUGUCACUAAAAGCCCACUGUGACAGAUAGUUCCAUUUGAAUUGAACUCAAUAUAUCUUAGUAAGUACAUUUUACCAUCAUUUUAAGCUAAUAUCCUUGUUCUCAAAAGGUAAAGUGAUUCACAGCAGACGAUGGUUCUGCCUAAUUUUUUUCUCAAUACUUAAAAAAUUACCUCAACACUUUAGAUCUUUCAUUUCAUUUUUAAUAGUAAUUCUGAGGUUUUUCAUCCCAUUCCUAACCCAGAGUUUGAGCACUUCCCCUAGAAACUACUUAGUGAUCCUGUGUCCUAAUCAGUCUCUUGCUAUGUGUUCUAAUUUAUUAAAGUUUCGUAUUGGACAUAAUACUGAGAUUAAUAAAAAUUACAGAAAUGAGUCCAGAGAAGAAUCUGACUCAAUAGGAUACCUCAGGGAAGCUUAUAGAUGUGUAACAUGGUAUUGAGUCUUCUCUUCUAGGAGCACUCGAUGUACUUGUCACUGUCCAGUUUAAAUAGGCCAGGGCCAACGUGGUGAUUUGAGAAAACUUAAAAAUUUGACGUGUGAAACCCAUGAUGUAACCAUAGCAGGAGAAAUUCUUCAAAUGAAAUUUCACCAAGAUUGGGUAUUUUGCCUUAAGUAAGAUUUCUACUACUUUUAUUAAAAUUCACUGUAGGGAUCUACUAUCAAUUAGCUUUCAAAUACAUCUGCAGCAAAUACUUUUGGUUCCUGUUUUGUAGGUUUGGAGUUUAAUAUAUUUAGUGCUAAGCUAAUUAGUUUUCUAAAAAGAUAAUUGCAAGACCCCUGCUUUACCAAAUACUUGACAAUGGGACUUUGAAGGUUAUUUCUUAUGUUUUCUGACUAGUAUGAUCUUUAAAGAAAAAAAAAAACACAUUGCAUACCUUUUAACUACCAAUGUUUAACCUCCUAGAUUUAGCAUUUAACUACAGCAUGUACCAUCAGGUCAAGAAUCUGAUAAAUGAUUGCUUGAUGUUGACAAAGUGAAAGACAAAAUGAAGUGUACUGAAGUAACUAAAAAUUCAGGAAGAACUUUCUUGUGCACACAUUAAUAAGUAACAUUGCCUUCUCUUAAGACCUAUCUGAAGUGUUGUGAAGUUUUUCUUACAAUUUUUUAAAAGAGAUUUAUGAAGAAACUAUGUGCUAAAAGCACAACAAUUAUUAAAUUUAUUUUCAUGUUGUUGUUUAAUUAUGGUUAACGAAUUGCCAGUUUUCAAGUCAGCCAGAGAUAAUACCAGAUUUCAGAAGUUUUACUCUGCUGUGAAGGAUUACGAGCUCUCUGAUUUUCAUUUAUGUUCCAAAAGAUGCCCAUAAUGUUGCUUUGGAGGACAGCAUUAGAAGUGAUGUUCCUAUUCAAAAAGGUUUUGUGGAUAAACCUUAAACUCUUGGCGGUGUUUUUGUUUGUAUUUGUUUUCCCAUUUUUGAAAACAUUUUCAAUCAUAUUUCUUGAGACUCAUUGGAAAUAUGUGAGCUAAAAAGGAAAUACUAAAUUGAUUUUAGAGAUGAAAAAAAAAUCUUCAGCAGCAGUGACUUGCCCAUAGUUCAAAAAGCAAAAAUUUACAAGUGGUGGAAGCAAAAGUAGAAUGCUGCUGUUGUGACUCCUAGGUCAGCGGUCUUUGUUGAAGCAAUGGAGUAAUAAAUCAAACGACUAAUUAAAAACAAAACAAUGAAAAAUCCAUGAUGCUUAUGAACAACGUUAGGGCAAUGAAUUUGAAAACAAAAAAAGGGAAGUCUAUUUUAAAAUAGAACUCAAAAGUAACUCAAGGAAUUGUUAAUUUUUUAAGUAAAUGAAUACAUCUAUAACUUUUAAAACACCACACAAUUAGAAUUUUAUAGAGAAUACAGUAAAUGAAACAACAACAACAAAAACAGGCAAAAUAAUACCAAAAUAGAUUUUUUUUUUAAAUGAAGAUGUUAGCAAACCAACUCCUUUAAAAUAACAAAAGUAAACAUCAACAAGUCAGUUUAAUCACAGGAUGGCAAGAUUUCAUCUCAAAAUCAUCACAUUACCAUUAGAGAAAAUCCAUGUGAAAAUUUGAACUGAUACUGAAAAAUAGUUUGAAAAAAUUCAAUACGAAUUAUUGCCUAAAAAACAAAGACAUUAACAAUAUAGAAACCAAAGCUCAAGAACUUGUACACACUGCAAAAGGGUAUGUACCAAAAAUCUACACCAGUUACUAUACUUAUUAAUGAAUACUUGGAAGCACUCCCUUUAAAAGCAGGAAUGGAAGAAACAAAAUUUUUACUGUUCUAAGAUGAUAUUUACAUGAACAAUUUUAUAGAAUCUAGAAACAGUUGUUCUCAGAUGACAUCUACAUCUACAUGGAUAAUUUUAUAGAAUCUACAAACAUACCAUUGAAAGUAGUGAGAAAAUUUAGCACAGUUACUGGAUAUAAGAUCAAUAUCUAAAAUCAGAAUACCAACAUUUAAAAAGUGUUAUUAAAUUUAGAAUGUAAUUCAACAAGUUAUAACAGUCCUAUGAAAUAAUAUCACAAGAACUGUGUAAGAUUUUAUAAAGAAAAUAAUAUUUUCUAAUAUGUUGGGAAAAUCCCAAGUAAAUGGAGAGAAGAUGUUCACGCACAGAAAAUGCAAUCAAUAUCAUUGCUCCAAAUUAUGUGAAUCGGAAGCAAUCUGUAUUACAAUCCAAAUAGAUGUGCUCAUGGAACUUGACAAAUUAAUUUUAAGAUUUAUAUGAACACCAGAUGCUAGAAUAGACAAGAUCUUUUUGACAGAUGUAUAUUUUAGUUUUGGUGCAGAAACAAUGGAAUAGAAUAGAGUUUAGAAUUAGAUCGAAACACACAGAUUACACGUUUAUGUCUUGAUGUGUGGUUAAAUUUGUAUUAUAAUCAGUGGAAUAUAAACCAGUAUUGUGGAACAGAUUAUCCAUAAAUAAUAAAACUGUGCUCAGACACAAAAUUAAUUCCUAUAUGGAUUAAAGAUUUAAUGUGUAAAAGUAAAAAAUGUCAAAUCUUUCUAGAAAAAUAUAGGAGGAUGUGUUCAUAAUUGUGUAUAAGGGGAAAAUUUCUUAAAAGUACAAAACAUAGAGAAAAGAUUGAUGUGUUCGACCAUAAUAAAAAUAGAACUUUCUGUUCAUUAAAUCAUACUAGAAACAAACAAACCAAUAACCUGAUGUGCUAGUUGUUUAGUUCUUAUAACUGAUUAAAGAUUACUAACAAAAUAGUUGUACAAUUGCCAAAUGUAUAAAGUAAAAGAACAGCUCAUUCUUACAAAAAGAAAUAUGAAUGGCCAAAAAGUUGUAAAAGUUCCCUUAGGUUCAAAGAAAUGCAAACUAAAAACAAAAUACCAAUUUACCCUACUCAGUAUGAUUAAAUUUUUUUAAAUGGUGAUGACAUCAACUCUGAAAGGCAUAUGGAGCAAUUAAAACACUUAAACUGCUAGUAGGCUGUAAAUUGGUAAAAAAUGUUUUUAAAAGCAAUUUAGAAAUACCUGUUGUGGUUGAAGACAAAAGUAACCAAUAUCCCAAUAUUUCCACCUGUUGCAGCAUUAUAUGUAAUAGGGAAAAAUUGAAAGUAAUAUACCCAUUUGGAAUACAUAUAGUCACUAUACUGAAGUGAGAAUAAAUUAACCAGAGCUGUACAAAUAAAAUAGUAAACCUAUGUUCUUAUACUUUGUUGCCUUUCUUUUGAUGUUUAACAAUAGGCAAAUCAAUGCUGUAUGUUGUUUAAAUAAUUGUGAAUAUGAAAUAAAAACUAUACCAAAAAUA